GUCUUUGCCCUCGCGACGCCGCCACCUCCGGAACAAGCCAUGGUGGCGGCGACGGUGGCAGCGGCGUGGCUGCUCCUGUGGGCUGCGGCCUGCGCGCAGCAGGAGCAGGACUUCUACGACUUCAAGGCGGUCAACAUCCGGGGCAAACUGGUGUCGCUGGAGAAGUACCGCGGAUCGGUGAGUGCGCGGGGUCUGGCGGCGCCGCUGGGCCCGGCCUCGCCCUGGCGGGGCCUGCUGGGGACGCCCCGCAGCCCGGUCCCCCGCGCGGUGUGGCUCCGAGGACGCUCCAGCCGCGCGGCCGCCAAACCCCGGCCCCCGCCCCGCUCGGCCGUGACCUCUGGCGCGGCGCCCCCAUCCCGCGCCCGGCCCGGCCCGGCCCGCGGCUACGUGGCACGGCCUUGGCGCGGAGGAACCCGAAGCGCUCGCAGUCGGCGCCCACUUCGCUACCGGCACCUUUGGGCAGCGGGGUCCAGACCUUCGCCGGGAGGCCGGGCACCACUGCCCAGCCUUUGCCAUUCACGGGUGAAAAAAGUAACCGUAGCAUCGUGCGGCCUUUCCCUCUCCCGUCCUCAUUUUCUGCAUCUGGAACGGGGAGUGGCUGAUUCGGAGUCCAGUGAAGAACACUGUGGAGAUCAAUGUGCAGGGCAGAGAGAGAGUUAUUUCAGAUGCACGGAGACCUCACACGGAUCAUCCCUGGGAGAGGGCACAAAGGCCCAGAGAGGGCAGGCAUUCGCACAAGGUCACACUACACUAGAAAGACGGGGCCUGGAAGAGAACCCCACCGCCACAUCCGGGGUCCUCUCUAGGCCAAGUCCUUAGAUGGCAGCUCAGGGGCACACAUAAGAGUCAUCCAGGCUAAUUGCCCCCUCAUUACCAAGAGGGAAUCUAAGCUCAGAGAAGACUUCGGAGAGGAAGGGUAUCUGGGUUGAGUCUUUGAAUACGAGUGGAUUUUAGCAAGACUAAGAAGCAAACAGCAAGAAGGGGGUGGGGGGGCGCGGGGCCAGGAGUUCCAGCUGUUGUGCUUCAAAGAGUCUAAAGCUGGAGGCUACGAGUGGUGGAAGAUGAGGCUGAAACGACUGGCAAGGGAGCAGGCGGGACCUUGAACACUACAUUGAGAGGCCUGCAUGUCACAUUAUGUGCAGUGAAGAACUCCCAGAGUGGACCUCUUCAGGAUGGACCUGGGGACUGGUGUGAAAUGGCUGGGGAGUUGAAAUCUAAUGAACAGGUGUCCCUGGUGGUGAAUGUGGCCAGCGAGUGCGGCUUCACAGACCAGCACUACCGAGCCCUGCAGCAGCUGCAGCGAGACCUGGGCCCCCACCACUUUAACGUGCUCGCCUUCCCCUGCAACCAGUUUGGCCAACAGGAGCCUGACAGCAACAAGGAGAUUGAGAGCUUUGCCCGCCGCACCUACAGUGUCUCAUUCCCCAUGUUUAGCAAGAUUGCAGUCACCGGUACUGGUGCCCAUCCUGCCUUCAAGUACCUGGCCCAGACUUCUGGGAAGGAGCCCACCUGGAACUUCUGGAAGUACCUAGUAGCCCCAGAUGGAAAGGUGGUAGGGGCUUGGGACCCAACUGUGUCAGUGGAGGAGGUCAGACCCCAGAUCACAGCGCUCGUGAGGAAGCUCAUCCUACUGAAGCGAGAAGACUUAUAACCACCGCGUCUCCUCCUCCACCACCUCAUCCCGCCCACCUGUGUGGGGCUGACCAAUGCAAACUCAAAUGGUGCUUCAAAGGGAGAGACCCACUGACUCUCCUUCCUUUACUCUUAUGCCAUUGGUCCCAUCAUUCUUGUGGGGGAAAAAUUCUAGUAUUUUGAUUAUUUGAAUCUUACAGCAACAAAUAGGAACUCCUGGCCAAUGAGAGCUCUUGACCAGUGAAUCACCAGCCGAUACGAACGUCUUGCCAACAAAAAUGUGUGGCAAAUAGAAGUAUAUCAAGCAAUAAUCUCCCACCCAAGGCUUCUGUAAACUGGGACCAAUGAUUACCUCAUAGGGCUGUUGUGAGGAUUAGGAUGAAAUACCUGUGAAAGUGCCUAGGCAGUGCCAGCCAAAUAGGAGGCAUUCAAUGAACAUUUUUUGCAUAUAAACCAAAAAAUAACUUGUUAUCAAUAAAAACUUGCAUCCAACAUGAAUUUCCAGCCGAUGAUAAUCCAGGCCAAAGGUUUAGUUGUUGUUAUUUCCUCUGUAUUAUUUUCUUCAUUACAAAAGAAAUGCAAGUUCAUUGUAACAAUCCAAACAAUACCUCACGAUAUAAAAUAAAAAUGAAAGUAUCCUCCUCA